GACCAUGGGCUCCAUGUUCCGGAGCGAGGAGGUGGCCCUGGUCCAGCUCUUUCUGCCCACAGCGGCUGCCUACACCUGCGUGAGUCGGCUGGGCGAGCUGGGCCUCGUGGAGUUCAGAGACCUCAACGCCUCGGUGAGCGCCUUCCAGAGACGCUUUGUGGUUGAUGUUCGGCGCUGUGAGGAGCUGGAGAAGACCUUCACCUUCCUGCAGGAGGAGGUGCGGCGGGCUGGGCUGGUCCUGCCCCCGCCAAAGGGGAGGCUGCCGGCACCCCCACCCCGGGACCUGCUGCGCAUCCAGGAGGAGACGGAGCGCCUGGCCCAGGAGCUGCGGGAUGUGCGGGGCAACCAGCAGGCCCUGCGGGCCCAGCUGCACCAGCUGCAGCUCCACGCCGCCGUGCUACGCCAGGGCCAUGAACCUCAGCUGGCAGCCGCCCACACAGAUGGGGCCUCAGAGAGGACGCCCCUGCUCCAGGCCCCCGGGGGGCCGCACCAGGACCUGAGGGUCAACUUUGUGGCAGGUGCCGUGGAGCCCCACAAGGCCCCUGCCCUAGAGCGCCUGCUCUGGAGGGCCUGCCGCGGCUUCCUCAUUGCCAGCUUCAGGGAGCUGGAGCAGCCGCUGGAGCACCCCGUGACGGGCGAGCCAGCCACGUGGAUGACCUUCCUCAUCUCCUACUGGGGUGAGCAGAUCGGACAGAAGAUCCGCAAGAUCACGGACUGCUUCCACUGCCACGUCUUCCCGUUUCUGCAGCAGGAGGAGGCCCGCCUCGGGGCCCUGCAGCAGCUGCAACAGCAGAGCCAGGAGCUGCAGGAGGUCCUCGGGGAGACAGAGCGGUUCCUGAGCCAGGUGCUAGGCCGGGUGCUGCAGCUGCUGCCGCCAGGGCAGGUGCAGGUCCACAAGAUGAAGGCCGUGUACCUGGCCCUGAACCAGUGCAGCGUGAGCACCACGCACAAGUGCCUCAUUGCCGAGGCCUGGUGCUCUGUGCGAGACCUGCCCGCCCUGCAGGAGGCCCUGCGGGACAGCUCGAUGGAGGAGGGAGUGAGUGCCGUGGCUCACCGCAUCCCCUGCCGGGACAUGCCCCCCACACUCAUCCGCACCAACCGCUUCACGGCCAGCUUCCAGGGCAUCGUGGAUGCCUACGGCGUGGGCCGCUACCAGGAGGUCAACCCCGCUCCCUACACCAUCAUCACCUUCCCCUUCCUGUUUGCUGUGAUGUUCGGGGAUGUGGGCCACGGGCUGCUCAUGUUCCUGUUCGCCCUGGCCAUGGUCCUUGCGGAGAACCGACCGGCUGUGAAGGCCGCGCAGAACGAGAUCUGGCAGACUUUCUUCAGGGGCCGCUACCUGCUCCUGCUUAUGGGCCUGUUCUCCAUCUACACCGGCUUCAUCUACAACGAGUGCUUCAGUCGCGCCACCAGCAUCUUCCCCUCGGGCUGGAGUGUGGCCGCCAUGGCCAACCAGUCUGGCUGGAGUGAUGCAUUCCUGGCCCAGCACACGAUGCUUACCCUGGAUCCCAACGUCACCGGUGUCUUCCUGGGACCCUACCCCUUUGGCAUCGAUCCUAUUUGGAGCCUGGCUGCCAACCACUUGAGCUUCCUCAACUCCUUCAAGAUGAAGAUGUCCGUCAUCCUGGGCGUCGUGCACAUGGCCUUUGGGGUGGUCCUCGGAGUCUUCAACCACGUGCACUUUGGCCAGAGGCACCGGCUGCUGCUGGAGACGCUGCCGGAGCUCACCUUCCUGCUGGGACUCUUCGGUUACCUCGUGUUCCUAGUCAUCUACAAGUGGCUGUGUGUCUGGGCUGCCAGGGCCGCCUCGGCCCCCAGCAUCCUCAUCCACUUCAUCAACAUGUUCCUCUUCUCCCACAGCCCCAGCAACAGGCUGCUCUACCCCCGGCAGGAGGUGGUCCAGGCCACGCUGGUGGUCCUGGCCUUGGCCAUGGUGCCCAUCCUGCUGCUUGGCACACCCCUGCACCUGCUGCACCGCCACCGCCGCCGCCUGCGGAGGAGGCCCGCUGACCGACAGGAGGAAAACAAGGCCGGGUUGCUGGACCUGCCUGACGCAUCUGUGAAUGGCUGGAGCUCCGAUGAGGAAAAGGCAGGGGGCCUGGAUGAUGAAGAGGAGGCCGAGCUCGUCCCCUCCGAGGUGCUCAUGCACCAGGCCAUCCACACCAUCGAGUUCUGCCUGGGCUGCGUCUCCAACACCGCCUCCUACCUGCGCCUGUGGGCCCUGAGCCUGGCCCACGCCCAGCUGUCCGAGGUUCUGUGGGCCAUGGUGAUGCGCAUAGGCCUGGGCCUGGGCCGGGAGGUGGGCGUGGCGGCUGUGGUGCUGGUCCCCAUCUUUGCCGCCUUUGCCGUGAUGACCGUGGCUAUCCUGCUGGUGAUGGAGGGACUCUCAGCCUUCCUGCACGCCCUGCGGCUGCACUGGUGAGCGACCACCCACUGGCCUGGGCUGCUCAAGGCGACAUUUCAUAUAUAUGGAUUUCACAGCUACACUCGAUCCACGCCCCACACCACAUACAGGCUGCUGUCUCCCACAAGAAUGAUGAUGUCAGGGGCAUCAGGAAAGGUAAGGGCCGGGAAACCGGGCCCUUGGAGAACCCUGCCCAGGGGAGGCCCAGCCUACUCACAGGAUCCGACACUCCAGGCAGAGCAGAGGGCAGGAGAGGCCCAAAGAGCUAGGUCAAGCAGCUGGCUCCCCUGGGAGGGGAGCCGGGAGACAGGGAGGUCCUCACACUGCCCCCGUGGCCACGCAUGGCUGUCUGCACACUCCAUCAGGAGGAAGGGCAGGGGAGAAGUCACAUGCAGUACAGUGAAACUCAUCAGUGUCACACACGCCCAGCAGGAGGGGAGAGCUCUGCUCCACACGCUGGCGGCCUUGGCUGCUCCAGAGCAAUCCGCUGCUCCAGCUUCAGCCAUGGGACCAAGAGGGUAAAGGAGCAGCUUCUGGAGGCCCCAGGCAGAGGCCACCUUGCAGCAGUGACUGGCGACUUUGCAGUACAUCUCUGCUCACUUGCUGUCCCUUGGGAGUGAGCACCGUCUAUAACACAUCGCCAUCUACAAAAGCCUGGUCACAGUGUUCACCAGCACAUUCAUGAAAAUUUAAAUCAACAUUAACCAAAGUACCUGCAAGUAACACUGCUUACUCUUGCUGUUUGCCUCAUCUGACUGGAAACCUUAGCCCCCAAAUAUGAAAUGCCUUCUCUAGAUUAAAAGGAUUCAGAGAUGUUGCACUAUUGCACUAUA